AAGUGGUGUCUGCCAGAUUUCCCCGCUGUAAAGUUACUAUUUGUCCCUUUCCAUGUUCUAUUCAUUAGUAGUGGGUGGCUAAGUCCAGCCCACACUGGAGAGGGGGAGUGCCAUCUGUUUUUAUUCCUAUCAUUUCAAUUUGUUUAAUCCUCAUGGCUUUAUUAUCACCUCACUACUUUUUAGAGAUAUGGUUGUAAUGAGCUAGACUUGCCCAAAGUUACUCAGCUAGUAAAUGGCAAAGCUAGAAUUUGAACUUAUAUGUGUCUGGCUUAAAAGGCCAUGUUCUUUCCACUUCAUGUUACUGCCACCAAGUAAAGAGGAUCUCACAGUCUCCGAGGCGGAAGCUCCCUCUCAGCUUGUCUGGACAGUGUUUUUCAAAUCCAUUCUUGGAGUGUGACCCAUCAGUGGGUCAUGAGAAGAUGAACACUGAAGUCUUGGAACCCUGGGAAUGAACCUGGAAAAAUUCAAAAUAUGGUCUAGUCUUAGGCAAGUUUCCUUGUCCGGCUCAGCUGCUGAGACCACAUAUCUGGACCCUCAGUGCCCUGGCAACAGCUCUGUGCAGGCAGGAUGAAGCACAGGCUUAGGUCAAGCAAUCAGCCGUCAAAAUCCACACUCUCACCUGUGAGUGGCUGUUCAACCUUGAACAUGUUACUUUUUAUGUUAAUGAAACUCAGUUUUCUAGUCCUAUAAAUUUGGGGCUAUCAUCAACCAUUAAGUGAUAUUAAACCCAGUGCCACACAGGCAAGUACCUAGCAGUGUCCAAAGGCCCCCAGAAUGACACUUUUUCAUCUUUUCUCUUCCCUCCAAUUGAAAGACUAGUGGAAUAUCUGCAAUUACUUUGACCAAAAGCCAGAAGCCGGCCAGUUUGAGUGUAGCUGUUACAGCUUUGUGUUCUAAACCUAAGAAAUGGGGACCCCUCACAUGAGAGUGGGGAGGCUUCUGGAUGUGCUACAAAUUCCAUUUCAUUUUCAUGAACUCCAGUGUUAAUUAAUAAAAUCUCAAGGUUCUCCCCCCUCUUUCGCCUCACAUUUCUUCAGAGAAAUGAAGAGUUCCAACUCAUAGCCCAAGUGCUCAGGUUUUAAAUUAGACAACUUUGUCCUGACAGGAACCAAGUCACAGCUGUCAUACCUGAUUACUUUUAGAGUUACUACUAAACCCUUUGUAUGGCAUGAGCUGCCACUGUUCAAGGCAAACAGAAACACUUCACAUUUUAUCAUGACAGCCCUGGAUCUAUCCACCUCCCCAUGUUCAUUAUGCUCAGCCUGUCUUUGGAAGGGAUGAUGAGGCAUCCUGAAAAUCGUAUAGUGAGGAAGGCAGACCCCAUGGCCUGUCACUACAGCCUAGGGAUUUUAAGCCCCUAAAGUGCAGCAAAACCCACUGCCUCCAGGAAGCCAAGGAGAAUUAUUUCUGGGGGACAUAGCUGCCUCAUAGCCUACUAUGAAUGAACCAUCAUCUUUCAUGAGAGGCAAACAUUGACCCUCAAGUAACCAACCAAUACGAGCACCUGUACACAAAUGCCCACAGGUGUUGGCUGGGAUUGGCUGGCUUGUGGAUGAUGUCACAGUUUCCCUCCUCUGACUCAACAAUGCCAUCAGCACUGAAAAGGCUGAGCCCUGACUACAGCUCUUGCAGACAGAAAAAUUCGCUGCAAGUACAGCACUUUCUAGAUUGCUCCUGGAGUGUGGGAACAACAGUCUCUCCUGUCCACGUUACUGAAUCCAGAAAAAAGGUGAACUUACGAACAUGGGAAAAGAAAUCCAGCUAAAGCCUAAGGCAAAUGUCUCUUCUUACGUUCACUUUUUGCUGAAUUACAGAAACAAAUUCAAGGAGCAGCAGCCAAAUACCUAUGUUGGCUUUAAAGAGUUCUCUAGAAAGUGUUCGGAAAAAUGGAGAUCCAUCUCAAAGCAUGAAAAGGCCAAAUAUGAAGCCCUGGCCAAACUCGACAAAGCCCGAUACCAGGAAGAAAUGAUGAAUUAUGUUGGCAAGAGGAAGAAACGGAGAAAGCGGGAUCCCCAGGAACCCAGACGGCCUCCAUCAUCCUUCCUACUCUUCUGCCAAGACCACUAUGCUCAGCUGAAGAGGGAGAACCCGAACUGGUCGGUGGUGCAGGUGGCCAAGGCCACAGGGAAGAUGUGGUCAACAGCGACAGACCUGGAGAAGCACCCUUAUGAGCAAAGAGUGGCUCUCCUGAGAGCUAAGUACUUCGAGGAACUUGAACUCUACCGUAAACAAUGUAAUGCCAGGAAGAAGUACCGAAUGUCAGCUAGAAACCGGUGCAGAGGGAAAAGAGUCAGGCAGAGCUGAUGGAUCCAGUUUGAAAAAACAAAAUGCCAUUCAACCGUA